AGGCUGGGCCGGUGGGAGAGGGAGGCGAGCCGACCGCUGGGCUGCUGGGCUCCCGCGCCCUCGCGCUCCCCGCCGCCAGCCCAGGCGCAGGCAGGGCGCAGGCGGCGGCGGGCGGCAUGGAGAGCCUGCUGGAGAAUCCGGUGCGCGCCGUGCUCUACCUCAAGGAGCUCACGGCCAUCGUGCAGAACCAGCAGAGCCUCAUCCACACCCAGCGAGAGCGUAUCGACGAGCUGGAGCGGCGGCUGGACGAGCUGAGCGCUGAGAACCGCAGCCUGUGGGAGCACCAGCAGCUGCUGCAAGCCCAGCCUCCGCCCGGGCUCGUCCCCCCGUCAUCGGCCCCGCUGCCGGCCGCUCCGGCCACCGCUCCUGCCGCCGCCGCCAGGGCCCAGGAACCUCUCCAGGACCAGGGACAGCGCUCAGCAGCCGCGCCGCAUCCCGCGCCCGAUCGGCCGCCGCGUCAGCACCACGGACAGCUCCUGGAGCAGCCCCAGCGGGGCCCUGGCAGCAGGGCUCACACACCCCAGUCGCCCCACAAGCAUCUGGGGACACAAGGGGCCGUGACUGACAAGGAGAAGGAGCGUCCCCCGAGUUGCUGCGCUGCUGCCGGAGCCCUCCUUCAGCACAAAUCCCCCUCCGCCCUCGGCAAGGGCGUCCUGAGCAGGAGACCUGAGAAUGAGACCGUGCUGCACCAGUUCUGCUGCCCAGCCGCCGACGCCUGCUCCGACCUGGCCUCCCAAAGUGAUGGCUCCUGCACCCAGGCCGGUGGGGGCAUGGAGGACUCCGUGGUGGCAGCGGCGGCGGUGGCAGCCGGCAGACCCAGUGCCCAUGCCCCGAAGGCUCAAGCCCAGGAGCUGCAGGAGGAGGAGGAGCGGCCGGGGGCAGGGGCUGCCUCCCCAAGGGCUGGCCCCCAGCACAAGGCCUCCCCCGGCCGGCAGCAGCCUGCCCUGGCGACGGCGCUGUGCCCCCACGCCCCUGCCGCCUCCGAUUACGAACUCUCCCUUGACCUAAAGAAUAAACAGAUUGAAAUGCUAGAACAUAAGUACGGCGGUCACCUGGUGUCCCGGCGCGCCGCUUGCACCAUCCAAACCGCCUUCCGCCAAUACCAGCUCAGCAAGAACUUCGAGAAAAUCCGCAACUCGCUUCUGGAGAGCCGCCUGCCACGGCGGAUCUCCCUGCGCAAGGUGCGGUCACCCACGGCCGAGAGCCUGGCGGCCGAGAAAGCGCUCAUGGAGGGCUACGGCCUCGUGGGGCUGCCGCUGGUGCGCUCGCCCUCCCUGCCGCCCACCUUCGCAGGCACCCUCACCGAGCUGGAGGACUCCUUCACCGAGCAGGUGCAAUCCCUGGCCAAGUCCAUCGACGACGCGCUCAGCACGUGGAGCCUCAAGACCAUGUGCUCCCUGCGGGAGAGUGGCGCUUACCAGCUCCACCAGGCCCUGCAGGCGGCCGCGGGGCCCCCAGGCCUGGAGGCCGAGGGGCGGGCGCCGGAGAGCGCGGGCCCCGGGCCCGGGGAUGACGCCGCGGAGACCCCCGGCCUGCCCCCGGCCCACAGCGGGACCCUCAUGAUGGCUUUCCGGGACGUCACGGUGCAGAUCGCCAACCAGAACAUAUCCGUCUCCUCCUCCACGGCUCUGUCGGUGGCCAACUGCCUGGGCGCUCAGACGGUCCAGGCCCCCGCAGAGCCCGCGGCGGGCAAGGCCGAGCAGGGCGAGACCUCUGGGCGGGAGGCCCCGGAAGCCCCCGCCGUGGGCCGGGAGGACGCGUCAGCCGAGGACUCAUGCGCAGAGGCUGCGGCUAGUGGGGCGGCGGAUGGGGCCACAGCCCCCAAAACAGAGGAGGAAGAGGAGGAGGAGGAGACGGCGGAGGUGGGGAGAGGGGCCGAGGCCGAGGCAGGCGACUUGGAGCAGCUGAGCAGCAGCAGCACGUCCACCAAGUCCGCCAAGUCAGGCUCGGAGGCGUCGGCCUCCGCCUCCAAGGACGCCCUGCAGGCCAUGAUCCUGAGCCUGCCGCGCUACCACUGCGAGAACCCAGCCAGCUGCAAGUCGCCCACGCUCUCCACCGACACCCUGCGCAAGCGGCUCUACCGCAUCGGCCUCAACCUCUUCAACAUAAACCCCGACAAGGGCAUCCAGUUCCUGAUCUCACGCGGCUUCAUCCCGGACACCCCCAUCGGUGUGGCCCAUUUCCUCCUCCAGCGAAAGGGCCUCAGCCGCCAGAUGAUUGGAGAGUUCCUGGGCAACAGCAAGAAGCAGUUCAACCGCGACGUGCUGGACUGCGUGGUGGACGAGAUGGACUUCUCCAGCAUGGAGCUGGACGAGGCCCUGCGCAAGUUCCAGGCACACAUCCGUGUGCAGGGGGAGGCUCAGAAGGUGGAGCGGCUCAUUGAGGCCUUCAGCCAGCGCUACUGCAUGUGCAACCCCGAAGUGGUUCAGCAGUUCCACAACCCCGACACCAUCUUCAUCCUCGCCUUCGCCAUCAUCCUCCUCAACACCGACAUGUACAGCCCCAACAUCAAGCCUGACCGGAAGAUGAUGCUGGAGGACUUCAUCCGAAACCUUCGAGGUGUGGACGAUGGCGCUGACAUCCCCAGGGAGCUGGUGGUAGGCAUCUAUGAGAGGAUACAGCAGAAGGAGCUCAAGUCCAAUGAGGACCACGUCACGUACGUCACCAAGGUGGAGAAGUCCAUUGUGGGCAUGAAGACAGUGCUGUCCGUGCCCCACCGCCGCCUGGUGUGCUGCAGCCGGCUCUUCGAGGUGACGGAUGUGAACAAGCUGCAGAAGCAGGCAGCGCAUCAGAGGGAGGUGUUCCUCUUCAAUGACCUGCUGGUGAUUCUCAAACUUUGCCCGAAGAAGAAGAGCUCCUCCACGUACACCUUUUGCAAGUCAGUUGGCCUGCUGGGCAUGCAGUUCCAGCUCUUUGAGAACGAGUAUUACUCUCAUGGCAUCACACUGGUGACCCCGCUCUCGGGCUCCGAGAAGAAGCAGGUGCUGCAUUUCUGUGCCCUGGGCUCGGACGAGAUGCAGAAGUUCGUGGAGGACCUGAAGGAGUCCAUUGCUGAGGUGACGGAGCUGGAGCAGAUCCGAAUAGAGUGGGAGCUGGAGAAGCAGCAGGGAACAAAGACACUCUCCUUCAAGCCCUGCGGAGCCCAGGGGGACCCACAGUCAAAGCAAGGAUCGCCGACAGCCAAAAGGGAAGCCGCGCUCAGGGAGAGGCCGGCGGAGAGCACGGUGGAGGUGUCAAUUCACAACAGGCUUCAAACGUCCCAGCACAACUCCGGGCUGGGGGCCGAGAGGGGAGCGCCGGUGCCGCCGCCAGACCUGCAGCCUAGCCCCCCGAGACAGCAGACCCCACCACUGCCGCCGCCGCCACCCACGCCCCCGGGCACCCUGGUGCAGUGCCAGCAAAUUGUCAAGGUCAUUGUCCUGGACAAGCCCUGCCUGGCCCGCAUGGAGCCCCUGCUGAGCCAGGCUCUCUCCUGCUACACCUCGUCGUCCUCUGACUCCUGCGGCUCCACACCCCUGGGCGGUCCCGGCUCUCCGGUCAAGGUCACCCACCAGCCUCCGCUGCCCCCGCCCCCACCCCCCUACAACCACCCUCACCAGUUCUGUCCCCCAGGCUCCCUGCUGCACGGGCACCGCUACUCCAGUGGCUCAAGGAGCCUGGUGUAGACUCUGCCCCACCACCCUGCUGUCCUGGGAGGGCUGGCCACUGGGGGGCCUGGGCUGCCCCUCCACUGCUCCCCAUACCCUGGCACGAUGCGUUCCUGGUCACUGAUCACCAUCAUUUUGGGAAGAGAAUCCCAAUCCCUGGCACCUGGGUUUGCCUCAUCCAACCAUCCUUCCCUUUCUCAGCUGCACCCCCUCUGCAGAUCUGAAGACACACCUCACUCUCCCAGGGCCCUACACAGCCAGACCCGGCGAGGCCUCCUCUUCCCCUGGCCACCACUUUCCCCCAUUGGACCAUGGACUGAAGAAAACGAGCUGAGGGUCUAACGAGCUUGCAGGCUUUGAGUCUGUUAGUGCCCGGGGCCUCGGGCCUUGGGCAGCAGCAUGAGGCUGGGCCGGCCGGCAGUGGAGCACUAGACAGAGUGGCUGGCUCGCAGCCCAGAACUAGUGCCUCUGUAGCUGCACUGAGGGGAGGAGGGUUGGUCCCACCCCUGGAGGGACAGGUGGGAGGAGUGAGGAGGGGGCUUUUUCUGCCACCCCCGCCCCCAAGCCUGAAACUCUCAGGAGUCUACUUCUUGGUCCCCAGGGACAUUGGCUGUCCUGACCAUGUCCUUCCCCCUCCUCCCAGGGCCUCUGCUUCCUCAGGAGCUGCCCAGACUCCAGAAAAGCCUGGAAAAAGGGAGGCGGGAAGGGGAGCACUUUCGGCUUUCUAUAGGUCAGUCCAGCAGGGCCACGGGAUCGCGAGGUCAUGUAUCUGCAAAAUGCACCUUUUUAAAGAGUGUCUUAGUUCCCCAGCCCCAGCUAAUACCCGGCCAAUGCCGUGUACGCACCGGCAUGUGCACGCAAACACGCAUGAGAACCAGGCCAUUCCUUCCGCUGUGGAAGCAGAACUGGAGACGGGGCAGGAAUGUGCCCAGCAGAGAUGGGGCUCAGCCCGAGGCAGGGCUCCCUCCUGCAUGAGGCUCGGCCCGAGGCAGGGCUCCCUCCUGCAUGAGUCUGUGGCCUCCAGGAGGGACUUGGGUGCAGAUGUAAGCAAGAAAAACCGGGGCUCCAGAGGCAUGUGCAUUUCCCCUGCGCCCCUCAGCCUUUAAAUAUUCCCUCCUCCUAGAAGGUUCUAGACCCCCCCCUUCCAGCAGGGGUGCCCAAGAGUCCCUGGACCCUCAAAAUUGCAAAGGAGACCCAAGCGGGGCUCGCUGACCUCCCAGGGCCCAGCAAGAUGGGAUAGCCAGCCUUAGGUGGCCCCACGAGCCCAAGCCUGGGGAAGGGCCCCUCCCCAGCCAGACGAGAGGCAGCCACCCCAGAGACCACAGGAGCCGUACCAUGGCCUGCGCAGUCAGGCCCUAUCAGGAUGUGUCUGUCCCAAGCCUGGCCAGGCUCCAGUCCUGUGCCAGUAGCUCACUGCUGUCCUAUGUGCAGGUCCCCCAACACUUGGAGCCUGUGGUUAAGGCCUCCUGGGAGAGGCAGUGAGCAUGAGUCAAAGGUGACAUGGACUUGAAUCUCCCCACCCCGCCCCGCCUGCAGUAGCCGGGCCAGGUAGGAGGCAAGGAUCAUUCCCUGCUCCCAGAGGUUCCAGAUGACCUAGUUUCGUUUUGUGUGUGUGUGUGUGUGGUCACCCAGACGUCACUGUGAUAUCACCUAGUGAAUCUAUUUCUGGCCCUGUCUUCGUCGGCCCAGUUUCUGUAACUUGCAGCCAAUUUGCCCUCUCCCCUGUGGCUGCCAGCCCAUCUGCCCCUCUGUGUCCUUGCUGCCCUGGCCCUCCUCUGUUUUCUGUAACAGAUGCUCCAGUCAUUGCCUUUCAGAGUGGAGCAGAUGACAGAUGGGGUGCACGCAUUCAGACACCUCUGAUGCCCUUAGCCAGGGCAGGGAUCGUCCUUAAAGUGAAGGCCUGGACAGGAGGAGUCAGGGACUUGGGAGGAGGUGGAGCUGUGGGGAUGGGAGUGGAGGAAUCAAAAUGAGGGAAGCUGAAAAUAGAAUGAAAACGAUGACUAAGAGGCAGGGAGUGCGAGGUAUGGGGGAAUAGGAACUAUGAGCUAAAUAUACUUAUGGGGUGGGGGCCGUGGGGGCCAGGGACACUCUCCCAGACAGCCCUGACCCGCCAGGCAGGACCCCGUCCCCUGCUCACACAGCUCUUCAAACUUACCAAGGACAGGCAGGACCCCGUCCCCUGCUCACACAGCUCUUCAAGCUUACCAAGGACAGGCAGAACCCCGUCCCCUGCUCACACAGCUCUUCAAGCUUACCAAGGACAGGCAGGACCCCGUCCCCUGCUCACACAGCUCUUCAAACUUACCAAGUGCCCUCUCCCCUGUUGAGGGCACAGCAACCCCAGGCCCUCCCUCCCACCUCAGCUGAAGCCCCAAUCUUCCAAAUCGGAACCAGCAAGUCUUAGGGCUGGCACGCAUCUGGGCCUCUAGCUGAGAACCCGGACUCUCAGGCACCUCAGUGCCCCUGCCCCAGGGCAGAGGCCCACCCCGUGGGUUGGUGCAGUGGCUGCCCUGGGCUCCACGGGCAGCACAGGGAGUCUGUCCAGGAAGCAGCCCAGCCGGGGUCAGUAUUCCGUGGAGCCAGUCCUGAGCUGGGAGGGGCAUUUAACACCCCUGAGGGCCUGGGGCAGGACACAGCUGGCCCUCCUCAUUGUCAGGGGAAGCAAGUGCCCAACAUCUGUAACCUCCCUUCCCUGCUCAGUCCCCAGGCCAAGGUUGGGACCCCUCUCCAUCCCUGUCCCCAGAGCCUAGACCUCAGGGACCUAGGAAAAGCCUCCUGCUCCCUCCCCACGGCAGCAGACAGGGCAGGGCCUCCAGCCCCCAGAGGGCCGGUGGGGGGUGCUCUCGGGCCUUCCUGCUCUCCUAAGGUUGCGGGGACAGUAGAGUGCUGAGCCCCAGACCCAGUCACCCCAAGAUGGCCCCACUCUAUCCACUCUCUAGACCUUUGGGAAAUCUGGGUCCCUCUCCUGAUUUGAUCCAUUCGGCCCCAACUCCAGAGUCGGGAAUGGGAGAUGAAACUAGUUUUCCACCCACUUUUGGACAAGUCCCACCCCUAGAUCUGAAGCAAGCUCUACCAGCAGCGUGUCCUGGAAGCCUGCCUGCCUGCCUGCCCGUCUGCACAGGUGUCUUGAUCCAGCCCUGCGUCUUCGAGCCCCUGUGCCACCGGUCCCCACGGCCCGCCAGGAGUCUCUUUGUACCCACUAGGCUUCCCUGAUGACCAUCUGUCUGUCCGUCCCUGUUUUUGCUGUACAUAACUCCUGCUGCACCCUCUCCCCGCACACCCGUCACCCAUGAGAGAGAGAAACCUCUCUAGGGAAAGGCAGGGUGGCUGCACCCAGCAACUAAUCCAAAUGGCAAAUAUUUUGUAACAAAAUAGCCCAGAGGUAUUUUAUCUGUUCAAUUCAUAGAGUUUUAGAGAUUAUAUUGAAAGAUGUCACUUGA